AGUUCCGGGGCGGUUGCUCACAUCGACCGGAACUCCCCGCCCCCUCCCGCGGCCCCUGGGGCCGUAGGAGGCCGCAGCGAGGAGGUAGAGGGGGCGGGGGUCGCACUAGGGUGUCCCUAGAGAACGAGGACUCUGAAGGCGGGACAUUUGGGCGACCCCCGGGCGGGGCCAGCCAUUAAACAGUCCCACUUCUGUGCCAGACACUGAACUGGGCUCUUGACGGGCAUCAUCUCUUAAUCCUCAGAACAUCCCAGGGAGCUCCACAGGAUCCCCAUAUCCUGGGCCAUGAGUGAGUUGAAAGACUGCCCCUUGCAGUUCCACGACUUCAAGUCUGUGGAUCACCUGAAGGUCUGUCCCCGCUACACGGCAGUGCUGGCACGCUCUGAGGAUGAUGGCAUCGGCAUCGAGGAGCUGGACACCCUGCAGCUGGAGCUGGAGACCCUGCUGUCUUCUGCCAGCCGGCGCCUGCGUGUGCUUGAGGCCGAAACCCAGAUCCUCACCGACUGGCAGGAUAAGAAAGGUGACAGACGAUUCCUGAAGCUGGGUCGAGACCAUGAACUUGGAGCUCCCCCCAAACAUGGGAAGCCCAAGAAGCAGAAACUGGAAGGGAAGGCAGGACAUGGGCCGGGCCCUGGCCCAGGACGGCCCAAAUCCAAAAACCUUCAGCCCAAGAUCCAGGAAUAUGAAUUCACUGAUGACCCUAUCGACGUGCCACGGAUCCCCAAAAAUGAUGCCCCCAACAGGUUCUGGGCUUCAGUGGAGCCCUACUGUGCUGACAUCACCAGCGAGGAGGUCCGCACACUUGAGGAGUUACUGAAGCCCCCAGAAGAUGAGGCUGAGCAUUACAAGAUCCCACCCCUGGGGAAGCACUACUCCCAGCGCUGGGCCCAGGAGGACCUGCUGGAGGAGCAGAAGGAUGGGGCCCGGGCAGCGGCUGUGGCUGACAAGAAGAAAGGCCUCAUGGGGCCACUGACCGAACUGGACACUAAAGAUGUGGAUGCCCUGCUGAAGAAGUCUGAGGCCCAGCAUGAACAGCCGGAAGAUGGAUGCCCCUUUGGUGCCCUGACGCAGCGCCUCCUGCAGGCCCUGGUGGAGGAAAAUAUUAUUUCCCCUAUGGAGGAUUCUCCUAUUCCUGACAUGUCUGGGAAAGAAUCAGGGGCUGACGGGGCAAGCACCUCCCCUCGCAAUCAGAACAAGCCCUUCAGUGUGCCGCAUACUAAGUCCCUGGAGAGCCGCAUCAAGGAGGAGCUAAUUGCCCAGGGCCUUUUGGAGUCUGAGGACCGCCCCGCAGAGGACUCCGAGGAUGAGGUCCUUGCUGAGCUUCGCAAACGGCAGGCUGAGCUGAAGGCACUUAGUGCCCACAACCGCACCAAGAAGCACGACCUGCUGAGGUGAGCGUUAGCAGGAUGCACAGUCCCGGGGGUGGCCUUGGAGGCUGUGGCCACGGCUAGUCACCUUUCAGGGGUUUUACAACAGGCUUUCCAAUCCUGGCUGGCCUCUAAAUCACCUGGAGAGCCUCGAAAAAAACAGCAGUGGCCAGUCCACCGGGUAUGUCCCAAACAAAUUCUGAUUCCACAGAGUGGGGCUCAGGCAUCUGUGACUGACCGAUUGAUUUGAUUUGUUUUUGUUUUGUUUUUUUUUGAGAGGGAGUCUCGCACUGUCACCCAGGCUGGAGUGCAGUGGCAUGAUCUCGGCUCACUGCAAGCUCCGCCUCCCAGGUUCAUGCCAUUCUCCUGCCUCAGCCUCCUGAGUAGCUGAUACUACAGGCACCCACCACCACGCCCAGCUAAUUUUUUUGUAUUUUUAGUAGAGACGGGGUUUCACCGUGUUAGCCAGGAUGGUCUCGAUCUCCUGACCUCGUGAUCCACCCGCCUCGGCCUCCCAAAGUGCCGGGAUUACAGGCGUGAGCCACUGCGCCUGGCCUAGUUUGGUUUUUUAAUUAUGGUAAAGGCAUAAUAUAAAAUGUAUCUCCAUGGGAGGCUGAGGCAGGAGAAUCAGUUGAACCUGGGAGGCGGAGGUUGCAGUGAGCUGAGACUGCACCAUUGCAUUCCAGCCUGGGCAACAAGAGUGAAACUGCAUCUCAAAAAAAAAAAGAAAAAAAAUUUACGCUUCUUAACCAUUUUUAAGUGUACAGUUUAGUAGUGUUACCCAUAUUCACAUUGUUGUGUGAUUUAUUUUUUGUCUUUUCAUGCUUCUUUUCUUUUUAUCCCCAAAGUUUUGUUAUUAAAAAUUUGAUACACACAGAAAAUCUGAAAGAAUCAUACAAUAAACAUCAGUAUAUUCUCCACCUAGA